GCGCUGCACGCCGGCGGCAGCCAUGGCGGAUGUGUCAGAGAGGACACUGCAGUUGUCCGUGCUAGUAGCCUUCGCUUCUGGAGUACUCCUGGGCUGGCAGGCGAACCGACUGCGGAGGCGCUACUUGGACUGGAGGAAAAGGAGGCUGCAGGACAAGCUGGCGGCGACGCAGAAGAAGCUGGACCUGGCCUGAGACUCUGCGCCUUCCGCCCCAUUCUGUCCCCCUCAUGGCCACCUUGCCAUGUCCGCGCCGGAGCCCCGGUCCGCCGGCGCCCAGAACCAGGCUUGCCACACAGUCCCCGCCUGCCAUGGCCGGCUCUUCCUGGAGUGUUGCUUGUUGAAGAUGCAUAUAGACUACCGGAAAGAAAUGACUUCUUCUUGCACUUUAUGAAUCAAUUUUAUUUUUAAAAUAAAAAAAUUAAACAUC